AACUUUGACAGCGGCUGGUCCCCGGAAGUUGGACGCAUGCGCCGUUUCUCUGCAUGGUGUGCGUUCUCGUUCUAGCUGCGGCCGCAGGAGCUGUGGCGGUUUUCCUAAUCCUGCGAAUAUGGGUAGUGCUUCGUUCCAUGGACGUUACGCCCCGGGAGUCUCUCAGUAUCUUGGUAGUGGCUGGGUCCGGUGGGCAUACCACUGAGAUCCUGAGGCUGCUUGGGAGCUUGUCCAAUGCCUACUCACCUAGACAUUAUGUCAUUGCUGACACUGAUGAAAUGAGUGCCAAUAAAAUAAAUUCUUUUGAACUAGAUCGAGCUGAUAGAGACCCUAGUAACAUGGACUUUUCAGUCGUGUGGCAUUCACUAAAUAAUAAAGUAUACCAAAUACUACAUUCACCGAAUUCCAAGAAGCCGGGAGGUUCAGCAGUCCUGGCCCUCCACCGUUUUCACCACCUUGCACUCCAUGUGGCUCUCCUUUCCCCUAAUUCACAGGGUGAAGCCAGAUUUGGUGUUGUGUAACGGACCAGGAACAUGUGUUCCUAUCUGUGUAUCUGCCCUUCUCCUUGGGAUACUAGGAAUAAAGAAAGUGAUCAUUGUCUACGUUGAAAGCAUCUGCCGUGUAGAAACGUUAUCCAUGUCCGGAAAGAUUCUGUUUCAUCUCUCAGAUUACUUCAUUGUUCAGUGGCCGGCUCUGAAAGAAAAGUAUCCCAAAUCGGUGUACCUUGGGCGAAUUGUUUGACAAAUGGCAACUGACUUCUUUAGAAUUUUGCAGUUAACAGUAGUAUGUACUCAAAUUGGGGGGAAAAAAACCCUACAUGUUUCUUGUAAAGGCGUCUGACAGUCCUGAGAAUUAUUGAUGGUAAGGAAUAAAAAAUGUACAGAUGACUCAGUGAAGAAACUGAGGCUUCUCUUAUGAAACAAACAUUGAUAAACGUAACUACUAAAUGUUUAUGCCUCUGUAAACCAAAUUUCUUUUCUAGAUAAAAAUAUGUAUUACUACCUGCAAAUUUUCUUCUGGCUGUUUUAGUAGUAUUUUUUUUACAGAACUAAAUAUAGAGUUUGUAUGAUUAGUAAUAUUUCCUGUCCUACAGCUUUUUUUUUUUUUUUUUUUUUUUGUAAAGUAUUCUGCAUUGUAAAAGAAGAGAGAAAAAAAGUAUUUCUGAGUUUUGGUUCAGAUACAAAAGGCUUUAUUUCCUGUAUGGAAACAGUGAUGUCCCCAGUGAAUCCUUUCAGCAUAAAGGAAGCAGUUAUAUUAAAUUGGCUUCAUGACAAUUUGCACUCCACAAGCCUCCAGAACCUUGAGCAUAAACCAGUAUCAUUUUUUGUACUUCAGUCUUGCUUUUUGAGUAGUUGGCCUUAAUACAGAGUAUCUUUUAAAAUCUCUUGUUUAGGCCGGCAUGACGGCUCACACCUGUAAUCCCAGCACCUUGGGAGGCUAAGGCGGGUGGAUCACUGGAGGUCAGGAGUUUGACACCAGCCUGACCAACAUGGUGAAACCUUGUCUCUACUAAAAAUACAAAAAUUAGUCAGGCGUGGUGGCACAUGCCUGUAAUCCCAGCUACUCGGGAGGCUGAGGCAGGAGAAUCGCUUGAACCCGGGAGGCAGAGGCUGCAGUGAGCCGAGAUUGCACCAUUGCACUCCAUCCAGCCUGGGUGACAAGAGUGAAACUUCGUCUCAAAAAAAAAAAAAAAAAACAAAACUCAAUGAUGUAGGGACUGUUAUUAUUCCCAUUUUACAGAUGACUUGUCCAAGAUCACAUGAGUAGUAAGUAGCAAAGCCAGAAUUCAAGUUCAGGUAAACCUGACUUCUUAGUGGGGCCAGUUUCACGGGUGUGUGGCCUGUGCAGUCACACAGAGUUCUGCACUGAAGAGGGCCUCCACUUGGUUUAAUGUUCUGCUGUGACUCUCUUGAACUUCUGAAUAUUUUUUUAAACAAUGAACUUAUAUUUUAGACCCUCUGAAUUCUUUCGCUGGUCCUGCUUGAGACUGUGUUUCUAGUGGUGCCAUGUCUACUGGAAUAGAAGUACAAUAGUUAGUGCAGUGCCUGGCCCAGGAGCUCCUCAAAAACAGGAAUUCCAUUUCCUUCCCUCUAACCUCUGCUUCUUUAACAAAGCAGCCAAAAAAAAAAAAAACAAAACAAAAUAAAAAACAGAAAAGAGAAGAUUCUCUCCUGUAGUAUAUAUAGGUUUUUUCCUCUUAAAUCUUUUGCUUUAUAAGUAUGAUAUAAAUCUAAUAAAUAGUGAUUAGUGAAGUGAUUGAAUUUUUGUGAAAAGAGACAUGAUUAUCCACGAUCAUGUAAGAUUAAAAUCCUGAGGCUGAUCCAGCCUUUUUUCUUUUUUUUUUUUUUAAAAAAAAAAAGCAAAAAAAACAAAAAAACUGUCUUCUCUGAAUCAUGUAACAGGCGCAUCUGUCAGCCGGACAUCUUCCUAGGUUUUUGGCUGGAGAAAUGUGUAGCCGAAGGUGUCUCAGAAUGGUGAGAACACUUUGCUGUCUGGAUUUAGUGGGCCUGGGGCAGCCAAAUGAUAGUUCAUUGUGCUUUGAUUUUAAUCCUCAAAUCUCAGUCACUGGUUGCUUCCCUGGAGUAUCAGAGCGUAUUAGUAUCAUACAACCAGGGGCUGAGGUGAAAUAAGCCUUGACUGUUCUAGAAAGAAAGUGAUUUUUUCAGGGACAACAGCAUCUGCAUUUUAUUGCUGUUUAAGGCUUUCUCUGCUCUGUACUUUGUUCCCUGAGUGGCACUAGGUAAAUGAAUGGUAAGGGAAAGUGAACUGCGUUUAGUGAAUGCCUCUCUGUGCUGUGGGGCAGCUUCCCUGGGCCCCCACAGGUAAUCCUGCUGCAGAGGCUUCUGUCAGGUCAGAGCUUAACAAAGAUCAGACCAGAGAGAAUUGUAGAAAAGAUGCUAUAAUUUUUUCCAGAAACAUAUGUCCCAGAUGUUUUGCAGAGCCUUAACUUAAGACAGUGGUUAGCCUGGAAUGUCAGAGAAAGAAUGUGUAUGUGUUAUAUCACCAAAAGUUUAGAAAUGUUAUAUCUUUCAUAGGUUCAGGCUGCUGUGUACUCAUUCAGAGCCAGGCUGAGACAUGUGUUAUUGCAUCUUCCUGAUCAUUCAGAUUACUCUGGUAAACAAGUGCAUGCUCUGCUGUGUGUUACUGUUAUGGCUAAUUUGAGUCCUCAAGGUCCCAUUAGCAGAGGGGGCUGGUGGCACAAUUUCCCUGCUGUGCAUUUCUGUGACAUUCAGAAAGAUAGUGCGCCAGUCCCAACUCAAACUGAAGAAGAUGAGUAGCUAGCUUGUCCCUUCCAGUUUCUCUUAGAACACUCUGAAUGCAACUUUUACUGUAGGAGACUGUUCAUGAAAAAAUUAAUUGAAUCAGUCUUCAAAUGAGAGGCAGGGAAACCACACAUCCUGCCCACACCUACUUCCCUGGAAGAUUUCUAUCUACAGUCCAGCUAUCCUAAAAGGUCUCAGUAGCUUGCCAGGUCAGAAUGUCUAACUGUUUCAAAAAGGAUGCCCAAAAAUCAUGACAGGAAACUUUAGCCUGGAACGAAGAGUGCUAUGAAACCGUGUCAACAAGAGGAGUGGUGACAAUUGUGAGUUGAAUAGCAAGAUGUCCUUGCUAGGAAGGAGAUGACCCAAGCUUCCCCUUAUAAAAGCAACUUGGAACACAUCAUUCUACCUUUCAAAGAUACAUGGUAAGUUAAAAUUGAGAAACGUACCCCUUUACUAUACAGUUCCUUGGGUUGAAUGAGUGCUUUUUUUUUUUUCUGAAAAGCCCCAUCCCCCAAAAGGCAUUUGAUAGCAAUGUAUUAAGCACCUUUUACCAACAAUAAGAACAUCAUUGUAAGUGUUAAAGAAAAUUGUCCUUCUCCCUACAGGUCAGCGUUUGAGCCUCACGGGGUUUCUUCCCAUGACUUCAGCCCUGGCGCACAAUGAGCAGACACCCAAAUCUUGUCCGCCUUCAACAUUCUUUUGUUAGGGCCCAUCCCUCUAGCACUCUAAAAACAAAUCAUCUACAACUGUGUUCCUGCUGCCCACUCAUUUUAAACAUGAAUUUGACAUAGCUCCUCCUUUUCGCACUGGAGUAGUUAACUAAUGCUAGCCCACUAGCUUCUAUCAUGUCCCUCAAGCAACAAACUUUGGGAUCAUUUUUGCUUUUUCACUCUUUCUUUACCCAAUUAUAAUUGGUUGCCUUUUUUGUUUCAUUAUCCCCAGAAUUUUCUCGUCUUCCUCUUCUCUCCUUGAAAUUACUUUUACUGUUCCUCUCCUUUGUCAUCACCUAUUGAUUCUGCCUUUGACUUAGUUCAUAUCUACCCUUUCCUUUUCAGUCCCAUAGUUACAACCUAAGCCAGCUCUUCAACAAAAAUUUCUUGCUUGAUGAGCAAGUUUUAUUGAGGAACUGAGGAAACACCUGUGGAAGGAACAAAUGAAUGAUUUUGUUAAUUACUUAUGUUUGUCUUCAGAGACUUCCCCUCAUGCUAGUUCUGUAUACUUGUUUCACUUUUUUCUUUCUUUUUUUUUUUUUUUUUUUUUUUUCGAGACAGUCUCGCUCCAUCGCCCAGGCUGGAGUGCAGUGGUGCAAUCUCACCUUACUGGCUCACUGUAACCUCUGCCUCCUGGCUUCAAGCGAUUCUUGUGCCUCAGCCUCCCGAGUAGCUGGGAUUACAGGCAUGCACCACCACACCUGGCUAAUUUUUGUAUUUUUAGUAGAGACAGGGUUUUACCAUGUUGGCCAGGCUGAUCUUGAACUCCCAACCUCAGGUGAUCCACCCAUCUUGGCCUCCCAAAGUGCUGGAAUUACAGGUGUAAGCCACACGUCCGGCCCUUGUUCCACUUUUUAUAAUAUUUACACCACAGAGAGGUUAAGUAAUUUAUUAAAGAUUAUAGAACUAGAAAGUGACAAAGCUCAGAUUUGAACCAAGGCAUUCUAGCUCCAGCCAGGCUUACCUUAAUAGCUACGUUAGGUGUUUUUUUUUUUUUUUAAAGAAAAAAGAAAAAAUGUCCUCAAAAGGAAAUAAAUGGGGUAACAGGGUACUAUGACGGAGUAGAAGGUAGUUGGUGUUCUAGAUAGGGAAAUCAGGAAAGGCCUUUCUAAGAAAGUGGUAUUUUACCUGAGUUCCAAAGGAUAAUGCCUUAAAUAUUUGUCCUCCUUCUACUUCACUCCCAACUUAGAUUUUGCCCCACCCACAAAGUCUUUGUCUUCAUUUAGCUUGAGCAAAUUCUCUAAAUAACUCUGUGACAUAGCCACCCAUACCAAAGGUUAGUGCUGAGUUAUAUACCAUCGAAUUGCAGUCCUUGUUCUUAGAAACACCUGUGGAAGGAAUAAUGAAUGCUAUUGCUGAUUAUUUAUGUUUGUCUUCAGGGACUGUACCUCAUUCUAGUUUUGUAUCCUUGUUCCACUUUUGAUAGUAUUUACACCACAGCUCUGUACAAAACAUAGGCACUAAUUAAAUACAUAAAUUAUUUGGCCAGGCAUGGUGGCUCACGCCUGUAAUCCCAGCACUUUGGGAGGCCAAGGUGGGUGUAUCACAAGGUCAGGAGUUCAAGACCAGCCUGGCCAAGAUGGUGAAACCCCAUCUCUACUAAAAAUACAAAAAAUUUGCCGGCGUGGUGGCGGGCGCCUGUAAUUCCAGCUACUUGGGAGGCUGAGGCAAAUAAUUGCUUGAACCAGGGAGGUGGAGGUUGCAGUGAACUGAGAUGGCACCACUGCACUCCAGCCUGGGGGACAGAGCGAGACUCCACCUCAAAAAAAAAAAAAGAAAAAAAUUAUAGCUUCAGACUUGUCUAGGCUCACUUCAGUUAUAUUUUAUCUAGACCAGUGCUUCACAAACGUUUUGAUCUCAGGACCUCAUUAUACUAAAAAAUUAUUGAAAACUGGCUGGGCACAGUGUUUCACACUUGUAAUCCCAGCACUUUGGGAGGCCGAGGUGGAUGGAUCACCUGAGCCCAGGAGUUUGAGAUCAGCCUGGGCAACACAGUAAAACCCCAUCUCUACAAAAAAAAUACAAAAAUUAGCCAGGCAUGGUGAUGCACACCUAUAGUUCCAGCUACUUGGGAGGCUGAGGUGGUAGGAUCACUUGAGCCUGGGAGGUGGAGGUUGCAGUGAGCCGAGAUCAUGGCACUGCACUCCAGCCUGGGUGACAGAGUGAGACCCUGCCUCAGAAAAAAAAAAAAUAUAUCCCAAUGAGCUUUUGUUUGUGUGAGCUAUAUUUGUCAAUAUUUACCAUUGUAGAAACUAGACAAAAAUUUUAAACGCAAGAAUAUAAAAGGACAUAUUCCACUGGCUGUCAGAACAAUAUCAUCACACAUCUUGUAGCAUCUGGAAAACUAUACCAUCAUAAGAAUGACAAGGAAAAGGCAAAUAACAUCUUAAUAUUACUAUGAAAAUAGUUUUGACCUCAUAAACCCCUAAAAACGUCUUGAAGACUCCCCAGGACCUUGGACCACAUUUUAAGAACUGCUGCUUUACAUAAUGUCACAUCAGCGAAUUCAUCUCUUCUUUUUUUAAAAUAAGAGGCAGGGUUUCACUAUGUUGUCCAGACUGGUCUCAAACUCCUGGUCUCAAGGAAUCCUCCUAUCUUGGCCUUCCAAAGUGCUGGAAUCACAGGCAUGCGGCACUGCGCCCGGCCUAUCUCCUCUUUAGUCAGUCAGUGAUCUGUGUAUUAGUUUUAUCGCUGUGUAAAAAAUUGCCACACAUAUAUUGGCUUAAAACAAUACAUUAUCUCUGUAGGUUAGAAAUCCAGGCAAAGAAGGUUUUCUGCUCAAGAUCUCAAAAGGCUGAAAUCAAGAUGAUGGCCAAGGCUGAGUUCUGAUCUGCAACUCUGAAUCCUUUUCAGAUACCUUCAGAUGGUUGUUGGCAGAAUUCAGUUCCUUGCAGUUGUAGGAUUUGUGGUGGCCUGCUUCCUAUCUUUUAAGGACUCACAUGACUGAGUCAGUGUAAUCUCCCUUUUGAUUAAUUCAAGGUCAACUGAUUAGGAUCAUAAUUACGUCCCUUUUGCCAUGUUAAUGUAACAUAAUCAGAGGAAUGACAUGUCAUGAUAUUCACAGAUCCCACCCAUACUAACGGAUAGUAGAUUAUCCAGGGCAUGUAAAUCAGGGGGUGGAAUAUUAGGGGACAUCUUUUUUUUUUUUCUUUAAGACGGAGUCUCACUCUGUCACCCAGGCUGGAGUGCUGUGGUGCAAUCUCAACUCACUGCAACCUCUACCUCCCUGGUUCAAGCGAUUCUCGUGCCUCAGCCGCCUGACUAGCUGGGAUUUCAGGAGUGCACCACCAGCCCGGCUAACUUUUGUAUUUUUAGCAGAGAUGGGGUUUCACCAUGUUGGCCGGGCUGGUCUCGAACUCCUGGGCUCAAGUGAUCCGCCCACCUCGGCUUCCCAAAGUGCUGGAAUUACAGGCGUCAGCCACCAUGCCCGUUCUGGGGGCCAUCUGAGACUUCUGCCAACCACAAUCAGCUAGAUGUUUUUUGUUUUGUUUUGAAAAAAUAAUAAUAAUAACCUUUCACUUGGGCCACCAAACUCCUACCUUAGUAUCCAAGUUCUCUAAUUUUUUUUUAAUAUGGGAAAUCCACAUCUCCCAAACUCUAUCCCUUUUCUGGCAAGUUACUUGACCUUUCUGUAAAAUAAGCAUAAUGUACCUGCGUUAGAGUUGUAGGGAGCACUAAACAUUCAGAUGAUGUAUGUACAGUGUUUAGCACAGAGCCUGCUAAAUAGUAAGCCCUCAAGCCCUCAGUCACAUUUGUCUCCAUCAGUGGUAGCUCCCCUGGUGUGUUAAGGAGGCUCUUCUUUCUUUUUUUUUUUUUUUUUUUUUUUUGAGACAGAGUCUCGCUCUGUUGCCCAGGCUGAAGUGCAGUGGCGCGAUCUCGGCUCACUGCAAGCUCCGCCUCCUGGGUUCACGCCAUUGUCCUGCCUCAGCCUCCCGAGUAGCUGGGAUUACAGGCGCCUGUCACCACGCCCGGCUAAUUUUUUUUUUGUUUGUUUUUUUUGUAUUUUUAGUAGAGACAGGGUUUCACUGUGUUAGCCAGGAUGGUCUCCAUCUCCUCACCUCGUGAUCUGCCCGCCUCGGCCUCCCAAAGUGCUGGGAUUACAGGCGUGAGCCACUGCGCCCGGCCAGGAGGCUCUUUUUAAACUAAGGGCAGCAACCCCCUAGGGUGGCUAUAGUCCAAGAAAACCCAGAAAAUACAUGCUGCCAAGGAUUUGGAGAAAUUGGAGCCCUCCUACAUUGCUGGUAGGAAUGUAGAAUGGUGCAGCAGCUGUGGAAAACAGUUCAGCAGUUUCACAAAAAUCAAACAUAGGGUUAUCAUAUGACCCAGAAAUUCUACCCAUAGGUGUAUACCCUGGAGAAUUAAAAACAUGUAUUUACACAAAAACUUAUAUGUUCGCAGCAGCGUUAUUCAUAAUAACCCGAAAGUAGAAACAACCCAAAUGCUCUACUAAUGAACAGAUAAACAAAAUGUGGUAUAUCCAUAUAGUGGAAUAUUACUCGAUCACACAAAGGAAUGAAGUACUAAUACAUGCUACAGUGUGGAUGAACCUUGUAAACAGUAGGCUAAGUUACAGAAGCCAGCCACAAAAGACAACAAAUGCAUGAUUCUAUUCAUAUGAAAUGUCCAGAGUAGGCAAGUCCAUAGACAGAAAGUAGCUUAGUGGUUUCCAGGGGCAGUGAGAAGGGGAAAUGGAGGGCAACUCCUAAUGGGUAUGAGGCUUCUUUUGGAGGUGAUGAAAAUGUUCUGGAAUUCGACAGUGGUGAUGGUUGUACAUCUCUGUGAAUAUACUAAAAGCCACUGAAUUGUAUACUGGGUGAAUUUUAUGGUAUCUGUAGACAUUCCAAUUGACAGUCACAUCUUAGUAUAGACUUUGAGUCAUCUCACUGGAGGCACUAGACAUGCAAGAGGAGAAGUCUCCAGAUUAUUCCAGCCCUGCCAUUUGAGUCACUCCAGGCUUUCUGGUCUUCCCAGCUGAGGCUCAGACACCUUGGAAGAGAGAAAAGCUCUCCCUUCUGUGCCCUGUGAUUUGCUGAUCCACAGAGUUCAUAGGCAUGAUUAAAUGGUAGUAGUUUUCCACCACGAAGUUUUGGAAUAAUUUGUCACAAAGCAAUAGGUAAUUAGAAAAAUAACCUUUCAGAAGGAGACAGUUUCUCCAAAGCUUGGGUACUUUCGCUUAAUAUUAAAAGAGGAAGAAAUUUUUUGCCUGCCAGGCAAAAGGCAGAAGAUGUAUUUCUACACCAUGGAUAGGAAAAUGAUUUUUUUUCCUCCUUUCUCCUUGGCCUGCAUGCAGCAGUGAAAAAGAAACCAAUGGAUUCUUUUAAAUCUUUAACCAUAUGCAGAUGAAUAAGCACAUGGUUGGACUUGAUUCCUAAUCUCUUUUCCUUUCCUGUAUAACUGAGAUUUUUUUCCACUCUAAUAAACUUGAGCAUUUAAACAGAA